GUUUCCCGCCGGCGUCUCCACCCUGCGAGAGCCGCCCGCCAGCCAGCGUCCGCCGCCGUCCGCGUCGCGCCACCCGCGGUCCGACGGGAGCAGGCCCAGCGGCCAUGGCCCAGGCCGGCGUCGUCGGUGAGGUCACCCAGGUGCUGUGCGCGGCCGGGGGCGCCCUGGAGUUGCCCGAGCUGCGGCGCCGCUUGCGGAUGGGCUUGAGCGCCGACGCGCUGGAGCGGCUGCUGCGGCAGCGUGGGCGCUUCGUGGUGGCGGUGCGGGCGGGCGGCGCAGCCGCGGCCCCGGAGCGCGUGGUGCUGGCCGCCUCGCCGCUGCGCCUGUGUCGCGCGCACCAGGGCUCCAAGCCGGGCUGCGUGGGGCUCUGCGCGCAGCUCCACCUCUGCAGGUUCAUGGUCUACGGCGCCUGCAAGUUCCUGAGAGCCGGGAAGAACUGUAGGAAUAGUCACAGCUUGACAACCGAACACAACCUGAGUGUGCUGAGAACUCAUGGCGUUGACCACCUGAGCUAUAAUGAGCUAUGCCAACUCUUGUUUCAGAACGACCCCUGGCUUUUGCCAGAAAUUUGCCAACAUUACAACAAAGGAGAUGGACCCCACGGCUCUUGUGCCUUUCAAAAGCAGUGCAUCAAGCUCCAUAUCUGCCAGUAUUUUUUACAGGGGGAAUGCAAGUUUGGCACUAGCUGUAAGAGAUCCCAUGAUUUCUCUAAUUCUGAGAAUCUGGAAAAAUUGGAGAAGUUGGGUAUGAGCUCAGACCUGGUGAGCAGGCUGCCUACCAUUUAUAGAAAUGCACAUGACAUCAAGAAUAAGAGCUCUGCCCCCAGCAGAGUGCCUCCUCUUUUUGUCCCACAGGGGACUUCUGAAAGAAAAGACAGUUCAGGUUCUGUGUCCCCAAACACUCUUAGCCAGGAGGAGGGUGAUCAGAUCUGUUUGUACCAUAUCCGGAAAAGUUGUAGCUUUCAAGAUAAGUGCCAUAGAGUUCAUUUCCAUUUGCCGUAUCGAUGGCAAUUCUUGGAUAGAGGCAAAUGGGAGGAUUUGGACAACAUGGAACUUAUUGAAGAGGCAUAUUGCAAUCCCAAAAUAGAAAGGAUCCUGUGCUCUGAGUCAGCCAGUACCUUUCACUCUCAUUGUCUGAACUUUAACGCCAUGACUUACGGUGCUACCCAGGCUCGCCGCCUCUCCACGGCCUCCUCUGUCACCAAACCUCCACACUUCAUCCUCACCACUGACUGGAUUUGGUACUGGAGUGAUGAGUUUGGUUCUUGGCAGGAAUAUGGAAGACAGGACUGUCCACCAGGAGCACCUCUGAAAUGUGGCGUGGGUGCCACCAGCGUUUUUCCUCAUCACGCAGUUUCUUGCCUUCAUAAAGUGUCUGGCUUUCCAUCGCAGGGCACGGUGCACCCUGUGACCACUGUCAGCAGUAGCGACGUGGAGAAGGCCUACCUGGCCUACUGUACACCGGGGUCUGACGGCCAGGCAGCCACCUUGAAGUUCCAGGCCGGAAAGCACAACUACGAGUUAGAUUUCAAAGCCUUCGUUCAGAAAAACCUGGUCUAUGGCACAACUAAAAAGGUUUGCCGCAGACCCAAAUACGUGUCUCCCCAGGAUGUGACGACCAUGCAAACCUGCAAUACCAAGUUUCCAGGCCCGAAGAGCAUCCCAGACUAUUGGGACUCCUCUGCCCUGCCAGACCCAGGCUUUCAGAAGAUCACCCUUAGUUCUUCCUCGGAAGAGUAUCAGAAGGUCUGGAACCUCUUUAACCGCACGCUGCCUUUCUACUUUGUUCAGAAGAUUGAGCGAGUACAGAACCUGGCCCUCUGGGAAGUCUACCAGUGGCAAAAAGGACAGAUGCAGAAGCAGAACGGAGGGAAGGCCGUGGACGAGCGGCAGCUGUUCCACGGCACCAGCGCCAUUUUUGUGGACGCCAUCUGCCAGCAGAACUUUGACUGGCGGGUCUGUGGUGUUCAUGGCACUUCCUACGGCAAGGGGAGCUACUUUGCCCGAGAUGCUGCAUAUUCCCACCACUACAGCAAAUCCGACACGCAGACCCACACGAUGUUCCUGGCCCGGGUGCUGGUGGGCGAGUUCGUCAGGGGCAAUGCCUCCUUUGUCCGUCCGCCGGCCAAGGAGGGCUGGAGCAACGCCUUCUAUGAUAGCUGCGUGAACAGUGUGUCCGACCCCUCCAUCUUUGUGAUCUUUGAGAAACACCAGGUCUACCCAGAGUAUGUCAUCCAGUACACCACCUCCUCCAAGCCCUCGGUCACACCCUCCAUCCUGCUGGCCUUGGGCUCCCUGUUCAGCAGCCGACAGUGAGCGCACAGGAGUGUUCCAGGCCUUUCACCUGCUCUGCCUUGAAAUGGCUAUUUGGGCCUUUCCUUUUCUUUUUAAACAGAAACUUUUAAUGAACUGUUCUCUUAACAUUGACCUCUCAAUGAAGUUAUGUUCUUAAUCUCUUGCUAAUAAUGAUUUUUACUUUUAAGUCACUUUUGGGUUCACUAGUGGAUUAACCAGAAGUGAUUGUAGUUGAGUCCAGUUUUGCUUUUUAAUAAUGUGUUGAAGUUUUAGUUUUUACUCUUUGUUGACUUUGCUGCUUAUUGGCACCAGGGACAGAGUUUCUAGAUACAAUUUUAUGGAUUGGUUUUAAUUUUUAUGAGUUUGUCUCUGCAGUGAUUCGGUUUCUCAGAGUCUCAUGGCAUCAUAGUUUUUCCAGAAUGACACAGUAGCCACCGGUGGAUGACAGCCCACGGGCGGCACAGUCACUUCUGCCUGUUGCUCUGACACCAACCCAGGCAGCUCUGCUGUGGCUUCUCCUGGGCUCUGGCAUUAGUUGGUCUGUGUCACAUUGUCAGAACAGGUGGCUGCUGUGUGGUGCCAUCGAGUCCCUGCUGGUUCCCCUUGUCCUGGGAGGGUCACCCAUUGCCCAAGGAAGUGCAUCCACCUGGCAGGUGACCUGGAGGAGUAGCUUCCCCGAGGACCCCCAGGCUUGGCCUGUGAUUGCGCAAACCCACAUUUCCUAAGCACACUGGACACCCUUCGAGUGUGGGUUUUAACAUCCCUGUGAGAUUGAAUACUUGUGCCACACAUGUCACAAAAGAGUAUGGAAAUAAAAGAAAAUUUAUCCGAA